ACUCGCUCUCUCCCUCUGUGUAUAGAGGAUGUGCUGAAUGGUGCGCUUUGAGGCGGCGGCGGCGGAGGAGCAGAAUCCGCCGCGACUGGCAGCCUCGGCUGACCGGCUCGGCUUCUCUUCGCCUUCCGAGGCUCCUCAUCCACCGCGGGCUCCAGACCUCGCGUCCCGCCCGGGGCAUGGCCGGGCGCUGCGCCCCCGCGCGCUCUGCCUGCUGAGCGGCGCCGGAGGGAGGUGCGGAGGCCGGGAGGCCGGGGAGGCCGGCGGGGAGCAGAGUCGAGCGCCUCCGGAGCAGAGAAAGGAGCCCGCGCCCCGCGCCCCGCGCCCCGCGCACGGUCCCCAGUCCCUGCCGCGCUCGCCCGGGCCGCCCGGAGCCCAGAUGAGCCCAGAUGGCCGGGGCUCAACCCGGAGUGCACGCCUUGCAACUCAAGCCCGUGUGCGUGUCCGACAGCCUCAAGAAGGGCACCAAAUUCGUCAAGUGGGAUGAUGACUCAACUAUUGUUACUCCAAUUAUUUUGAGGACUGACCCUCAGGGAUUUUUCUUUUACUGGACAGAUCAAAACAAGGAGACAGAGCUACUGGAUCUCAGCCUUGUCAAAGAUGCCAGAUGUGGGAGACACGCCAAAGCUCCCAAGGACCCCAAAUUACGUGAACUUUUGGAUGUGGGGAACAUCGGGCGCCUGGAGCAGCGCAUGAUCACAGUGGUGUAUGGGCCUGACCUCGUGAACAUCUCCCAUUUGAAUCUCGUGGCUUUCCAAGAAGAAGUGGCCAAGGAAUGGACAAAUGAGGUUUUCAGUUUGGCAACAAACCUGCUGGCCCAAAACAUGUCCAGGGAUGCAUUUCUGGAAAAAGCCUAUACUAAACUUAAGCUGCAAGUCACUCCAGAAGGGCGUAUUCCUCUCAAAAACAUAUAUCGCUUGUUUUCAGCAGAUCGGAAGCGAGUUGAAACUGCUUUAGAGGCUUGUAGUCUUCCAUCUUCAAGGAAUGAUUCAAUACCUCAAGAAGAUUUCACUCCAGAAGUGUACAGAGUUUUCCUCAACAACCUUUGCCCUCGACCUGAAAUUGAUAACAUCUUUUCAGAAUUUGGUGCAAAAAGCAAACCAUAUCUUACCGUUGAUCAGAUGAUGGAUUUUAUCAACCUUAAGCAGCGAGAUCCUCGGCUUAAUGAAAUACUUUAUCCACCUCUAAAACAAGAGCAAGUCCAAGUAUUGAUUGAGAAGUAUGAACCCAACAACAGCCUCGCCAGAAAAGGACAAAUAUCAGUGGAUGGGUUCAUGCGCUAUCUGAGUGGAGAAGAAAACGGAGUCGUUUCACCUGAGAAACUGGAUUUGAAUGAAGACAUGUCUCAGCCCCUUUCUCACUAUUUCAUUAAUUCCUCGCACAACACCUACCUCACAGCUGGCCAACUGGCUGGAAACUCCUCUGUUGAGAUGUAUCGCCAAGUGCUCCUGUCUGGUUGUCGCUGUGUGGAGCUGGACUGCUGGAAGGGACGGACUGCAGAAGAGGAACCUGUCAUCACCCAUGGCUUCACCAUGACAACUGAAAUAUCUUUCAAGGAAGUGAUAGAAGCAAUUGCGGAGUGUGCAUUUAAGACUUCACCUUUUCCAAUUCUCCUUUCGUUUGAGAACCAUGUGGAUUCCCCAAAGCAGCAAGCCAAGAUGGCGGAGUACUGCCGACUGAUCUUUGGGGAUGCCCUUCUCAUGGAGCCCCUGGAAAAAUAUCCACUGGAAUCUGGAGUUCCUCUUCCAAGCCCUAUGGAUUUAAUGUAUAAAAUUUUGGUGAAAAAUAAGAAGAAAUCACACAAGUCAUCAGAAGGAAGCGGCAAAAAGAAGCUCUCAGAACAAGCCUCCAACACCUACAGUGACUCCUCCAGCAUGUUCGAGCCCUCAUCCCCAGGAGCCGGAGAAGCUGAUACGGAAAGUGACGACGACGAUGAUGAUGAUGACUGUAAAAAAUCUUCAAUGGAUGAGGGGACUGCUGGAAGUGAGGCUAUGGCCACAGAAGAAAUGUCUAAUCUGGUGAACUAUAUUCAGCCAGUCAAGUUUGAGUCAUUUGAAAUUUCAAAAAAAAGAAAUAAAAGUUUUGAAAUGUCUUCCUUCGUGGAAACCAAAGGACUUGAACAACUCACCAAGUCUCCAGUGGAAUUUGUAGAAUAUAACAAAAUGCAGCUUAGCAGGAUAUAUCCAAAAGGAACACGUGUGGAUUCAUCCAACUAUAUGCCUCAGCUCUUCUGGAAUGCAGGUUGUCAGAUGGUGGCACUUAAUUUCCAGACAAUGGACCUGGCUAUGCAAAUAAAUAUGGGGAUGUAUGAAUACAACGGGAAGAGUGGCUACAGAUUGAAGCCAGAGUUCAUGAGGAGGCCUGACAAGCAUUUUGAUCCAUUUACUGAAGGCAUCGUAGAUGGGAUAGUGGCAAACACUUUGUCUGUUAAGAUUAUUUCAGGUCAGUUUCUUUCUGAUAAGAAAGUUGGGACUUACGUGGAAGUAGAUAUGUUUGGUUUGCCUGUGGAUACAAGGAGGAAGGCAUUUAAGACCAAAACAUCCCAAGGAAAUGCUGUGAAUCCUGUCUGGGAAGAAGAACCUAUUGUGUUCAAAAAGGUGGUUCUUCCUACUCUGGCCUGUUUGAGAAUAGCAGUUUAUGAAGAAGGAGGUAAAUUCAUUGGCCACCGUAUCUUGCCAGUGCAAGCCAUUCGGCCAGGCUAUCACUAUAUCUGUCUAAGGAAUGAAAGGAACCAGCCUCUGACGCUGCCUGCUGUCUUUGUCUACAUAGAAGUGAAAGACUAUGUGCCAGACACAUAUGCAGAUGUCAUCGAAGCUUUAUCAAACCCAAUCCGAUAUGUGAACCUGAUGGAACAGAGAGCUAAGCAAUUGGCUGCUUUGACACUGGAAGAUGAAGAAGAAGUAAAGAAAGAGGCUGAUCCUGGAGAAACACCAUCAGAGGCUCCAAGUGAAGCGAGAACGACUCCAGCAGAAAAUGGGGUGAAUCACACUACAACCCUGACACCCAAGCCACCCUCCCAGGCUCUCCACAGCCAGCCAGCUCCAGGUUCUGUAAAGGCACCUGCCAAAACAGAAGAUCUUAUUCAGAGUGUCUUAACAGAAGUGGAAGCACAGACCAUCGAAGAACUAAAGCAACAGAAAUCGUUUGUGAAACUUCAAAAGAAACACUACAAAGAAAUGAAAGACCUGGUUAAGAGACACCACAAGAAAACCACUGACCUUAUCAAAGAACACACUACCAAGUAUAAUGAAAUUCAGAAUGACUACUUGAGAAGGAGAGCCGCUUUGGAAAAGUCCGCCAAAAAGGACAGUAAGAAAAAAUCGGAACCCAGCAGCCCUGAUCAUGGUUCAUCAACGAUUGAGCAAGACCUCGCUGCUCUGGAUGCUGAAAUGACCCAAAAGUUAAUAGACUUGAAGGACAAACAACAGCAGCAGCUGCUUAAUCUUCGGCAAGAACAGUAUUAUAGUGAAAAAUACCAGAAGCGAGAACAUAUUAAACUGCUUAUUCAAAAGUUGACGGAUGUCGCAGAAGAGUGUCAGAACAAUCAGUUAAAGAAGCUCAAAGAAAUCUGUGAGAAAGAAAAGAAAGAAUUAAAGAAGAAAAUGGAUAAAAAGAGGCAGGAGAAGAUAACAGAAGCUAAAUCCAAAGACAAAAGUCAGAUGGAAGAGGAGAAGACAGAGAUGAUCCGGUCAUAUAUCCAGGAAGUGGUGCAGUAUAUCAAGAGGCUAGAAGAAGCGCAAAGUAAACGGCAAGAAAAACUCGUAGAGAAACACAAGGAAAUACGUCAGCAGAUCCUGGAUGAAAAGCCCAAGGGGGAAGGUUCCUCCUCAUUCUUGUCGGAAACUUGCCAUGAGGAUCCCUCUGUUUCCCCCAACUUUACUCCCCCCAACCCUCAAGCUCUCAAGUGGUGACCACCGUCCUUCCGGCCAGCUGCAGGUGGAGCUGGAGCAAGAAUACCAAGACAAAUUCAAAAGACUGCCCCUCGAGAUUUUGGAAUUCGUGCAGGAAGCCAUGAAAGGAAAGAUCAGUGAAGACAGCAAUCACGGUUCUGCCCCUCUCUCCCUGUCCUCAGACCCUGGAAAAGUGAACCACAAGACUCCCUCCAGUGAGGAGCUGGGAGGAGACAUCCCAGGAAAAGAAUUUGAUACUCCUCUGUGAAUGCUCCUGCCAGGCCUUCAGAAAUUGCAUGGCCACUCCAGCGUCAUCGGACUCUCUCUUAUUACAAAGAUCACUGCCCAGGACCAUCUUCCCGAGAAGCAUCCCUUAGCCUAAAAUCCACACCAAAGGGAGAGUUCCAGAGGAAUCCAUGAAGAAUUCCCAUGCCCAGGCUCCAUGUGUCAUGUGGAAACCUCCACAGGUCUGCUAGUGAAGAAUGCAUGUAUGUGAGAUUUUUGUUUUCUUUCCAAUAGCAAAUUCAAAGCAAGCAACUUGCAGGCUCCAUGGAACUUUUAAUGAAGGACAGUGUCUUCUUUGAAGAAAAUCAAGCUCGUGUUUUUAUUCGAAGCUCUGGUGUAAAAUAUUUCAAAGUCAUAGAAAUAGUUUGAGAAAUGCAUAGCAUUAUUUAACACUAUUGAACAGCCGACUUUGAGCAUUGUUUCUUCUAACUGCCCCUCAACUACCAUUAUCUUCAAGUCAACAUGCAUAUUACAUUUUCAUCCUUUGCUUUGCAAGCACUGGUGGCUUGCAGUUUGCUAAUUUAUUUAUCAUAGAGUCAUCAAUGUAUUUGUUGCUGACAUGGUUUUAUUAGAUACUGUAGUGAUUCAAAUAAGUUUUCUAUUUGAAAAAAAAAAUCACUUGAUUGUAUCCUUGCCCAGUGAAGCCAUCCUAAGACUUAGCAAUAUGGAUUGUACAUUUGGCUGCAUGAGCAAGUCGGCCGCACACUUCCAGACAGUGUGCUGUUUGAAUUGACUAUUUGCACUCAAAGUCUGGGUAUUCAUUGGUUAUUGGCCUGAAAUGAUCAAAUAACUACAAAUGAUCUGUUGAAUAAAAAUAGUUGAGCUGAUAUAUGUUAAGCAGAUAUUCAAUCAGAAUGAACAGGUUCCGGUGGUUAUUUUGCCGUUUGACAUUUUUUAUGGUUCAUUUAUUUUUAAUAUAGAGAGGAAGAUUGAAUAUUUAUCUAGAGAAUACAAAGACCCACAUGUAAAUGAUAGGUAUUAUCUCCAUGUAUAUAUGUACCCACUUAGUCAUGUAAGUGCAUAUACACAUACACACACAUGAGUGUAGACAUGUGUUUAUUAAUUGACAAUGACCCAAAUCUCUUCCACAAGACUUAAAACCAAAUUCAGGGACAAAUGGAUAGAGAAGAAAAGGGUCAAACAUCGAGAUUACAUGGAUGUUAAAUUAUAUGGAGACGCUAAGAAAUAAUUGAUGGAGCCAUUGAUGCAAACCGAAGUAGAUUUAGAACUUAUAUGAAUUUGAUUUAUAUUUUGCAAGAUCAAAAAUUAGAUGUUAAGUAUCAGAUUUUAAGCUUGUUUUAAUGGUCAAAAAAUUAGGACAGAAAUAAUAUGGACAUUUAUUAGUAUCUUCCAUAAUUUUUAAGUCUGACACAUUUCUAUUUUAUUCUAACAUAAAAAAACUUCCAUUAUAUAUUUACUAAGUAUAUUUAAUUCACUUAACUCUGUCUUUAUAAGUUCCUAUUUUAGAUGGAAUAAGAGAAACAAAUUAUAUCAAGGUAAAACUGAUCAAAAGCAUAAUUGAAAGUUCUGAAAAAAGAAAAAUAAUAAUAUGUAGAAAAAUGUAACUUAGAGAGUAACACAUGAACAUUGAAGUUAAAACCCAGAAGCCAGAUGCUCACAGUUUUAUUUUACUUUAAAAUAAACCUGUCUGACUGUAGCUUUGUGAAAUAUCUUAAAACGCAAAAACCAAUUGUGUCCUGAAAAUUGUUUCAAGAAUUUAAUAUUUUUAUGAAAAUUAUUUUAUUUAACUUUAAGCAAUAACUAGAGAUUACAAUUAAAUUUUAAUCAAAAUGAAGGCUUAGUUCAAACAUAAGGAAACAGUGUUUGAUUAAAAAAAACACAUCUAGUAAGACGUAAGGGGAAAAUCACAUCCUCUUUGGAGAUGAUUAUAUUUUGAUCUGAAGGGUUUGGGGUGUUCAUUAGACACUUAAUAAAACUUAACUUCCAAUGAAAAAGAAAUCUUUUGUAAAUCAUUCUACUUUUGCACUUUGAAAGAAAGGCGUUAAUCAUAAAGAAGCAAGAAUGGUCAAAAUCGAAUGCUGCAUUUUUAUAAACAAAAUUACAGACUGUCUGAAAUUGAAGAAGAAUGAACUAAUAAUAGCAUUCAUAACCAAACACAAUGAUGAUUAUUGCAGAACAUUGUAUCACAUUUUAGUCCAGAGAUAGAAUAAAGUUGAAUAACCUUGACUUACACAAAACUGUUUUGGUAGUUGGAUUUCAUUAUCUUAGUGAAUUUAGUCAUUUUACAAUAUGUUUGUAUUUGGCCAUUUACUGUAAUCACAUUUUUAUAUCUGUACAAUGACACUUUUUGCAGUUGUGGGGUAGUGUGUAACACUGUCCAUCUUGCAUCAUUGAAACUACUACAAUGAUACUAUCAUUUAAUAAUAUUAAUAUUACUUGAAAUAGACUAAGAUAAAGAAAAGGGGUCUGUAUGAUGUGCAGUUUUGUGCCUUUAUGUAUUUGCCUUGUUCUUUGUCGAAUGUGUGAAAUUCCGUACUGUGGUUUUUCCUAUAAUAGAAAGUAGAGCUGUGUAUUAAAUUAGACUGUGUCUCUCUGAUACCUUUACACUACUGAGAAUAGCAUGGUUUUGGCCAUGUAAACCAAUUUUCAAAGUUCUAAUGACAUAGCCAUGUGUUUUUGGUUUUUUAUAUUUCAUUUUAAAAUUUGAGUAUCACCAUACAUUAAUUAAUACUCCUGUAGUAGAUAAGCUGUCAUUAAGUAAUUCCCAAAAAAAGGGCCAUUUGCUUGCAUUACUUUGAAUUUAAUGUUGCGCUUGUGCACUGUGUUAAUAUUGUUUGUGAUGGAUUGGACGUUGUGACUCUUGCCUUUUAAGAAGAAAAAAAAGAUAGGACAAAGUAUUUGAAGCUCUUAAAAUGUACAUAUUUUGGUUCUUCUAUCUCAAAUUAUUUAAAAUGCAUAAUUCACAUUUUUGUAAUAAUUCUAUGCAAUUUUGUGGCAUGAUGUUUCUUCCACUUGUAAUUUUAUGUGCUUUCAUCACAAAUCCAAAGGAAAGAAUAAAAAUUUCUUAACACAA